GAGGCCUGAGUGAGUUUGGGCACACUCUGUGUGAUCGGGCAGAAGGCCUGUGGGAAGUUCAGCUGAGGACAGGGCCAGGAAAGGUGAUGGACAGUGGGGGUCUGUCCUGGUCACCAGACCCCUGGGUCCUGCCCACCUGCUUGGAGCUCCCCACCCAUCACACAUGAUGCUGCCAAGCCCUCUGGGUAUUGUGGGCAAAUACCUUAGGAGAGAAGCUGAUGAACUUUGUUUCUUGAAAUGCACAGAUUCCUUGGACGUCCCUGAGAGGUCAAUGAUGAAGGUCAACUUGGUUUUCUCCCCCUCAUUUGGGUUCAGAAUUUAAAGUCCACACACACAGGCAGUAAGAUGAUUAUAGAUAAGGACAUCAUCACUCGGUUUCAGAUGUUAAAAUGUCUAGGUGGGUUAGGGGUGAUUUGAGAUCACACAACCUUGUGCCACAAAGAGGAAUUCCCAGGCCAGGGGGAGACAUUUUAUUGCCAUGUUAUGAUCUCAUCAUUGAGUUGAAAGGCAAUCUUGUUUCAUUUUGGAUUCUUUCUUAUGUUUAUGUCUUAUAAGGGCACUUUGAAUUUCCAAGCAAAUAAUAAUUUUGAAUUAGCUUUUAAUCAUUGACUUCUAGCACAGUUAUAUGAUCAGAAACAUGCUGUGUGAUUUGAUUGCUCUCAAAUAUAUUGAGAUUUGCUGGAACAAAAUAAGUCAGGUUAAUUUUUGUAAAUGUACCAUGCAUGCUUAAAAUGAAUGUAUCUACAUUUGUUCCUGAGAUACAGGUUGAUGGACGGAUGGCUACAUGGAUGUGAUGGAGAUGGUUUACUAUCGGGACCUUCCGCAUCCUGCUGAUGUUUUGUUGCUUAGGAUAUGAAUGGCUGAGCGGAGGCUGUAAAACCUGGCACUCUGCUUGGGUAUGAAGUUCUUCCUGCCAUCCUGCCAUCAUUUGUUUUUUAUGUUUUGUCGCCAAAAGUGACCUUGAGGAACCCUGGGAGCUCAGGAAGGAAGGAGAGCCCAGAAGCAGGGACAGGGAGCUGGUUGGGGAGGACCAGAAAUCAGGGCGCCCUGAAAGGACCAGGACAUGCGGCUGCGCUUUUGGCUCCUCAUUUGGCUCCUGCUGGGAUUUAUCAGCCAUCAGCCCACCCCUGUCAUCAAUAGUCUGGCUGUCUAUCGUCAUCGUGAGACUGACUUUGGUGUAGGAGUUCGAGACCACCCUGGCCAACAUGGCAAAACCCCAUCUCCACAAAAAUUGGAUAAUUUGAUAAUUAUCAUUAUUGGGUUUCUGAGACGUGACACAUUUACCAUUCUCUUCUGCACAAGUUACCUUUGUGUGUCUUUCCUGAAGACUAUCUUCUGGUCUCGAAAUGGACAUGAUGGAUCCACGGAUGUACAGCAGAGAGCCUGGAGGUCCAACCGCAGUAGACAGAAAGGGCUGAGGUCCAUUUGUAUGCACACAAAGAAAAGAGUUUCUUCCUUUCGAGGAAAUAAAAUUGGCCUGAAAGACGUCAUUACUCUACGGAGGCAUGUGGAAACAAAAGUUAGAGCUAAAAUCCGUAAGAGGAAGGUGACAACGAAAAUCAACCGUCAUGACAAAAUCAAUGGAAAGAGGAAGACCGCCAGAAAACAGAAAAUGUUUCAACGUGCGCAAGAGUUGCGGCGGCGGGCAGAGGACUACCACAAAUGCAAAAUCCCCCCUUCUGCAAGAAAGCCUCUUUGCAACUGGGUCAGAAUGGCGGCAGCGGAGCAUCGUCAUUCUUCAGGAUUGCCCUGCUGGCCCUACCUCACAGCUGAAGCUUUAAAAAACAGGAUGGGCCGCCAGCCACCUCCUCCAACUCAACAACAUUCUAUAACUGAUAACUCCCUGAGCCUCAAGACACCUCCCGAAUGUCUCCUUCAUCCCCUUCCACCCUCAGUGGAUGAUAAUAUCAAGGAGUGUCCUCUUGCUCCUCUUCCACCCUCAGUGGAUGAUAAUCUGAAGGAGUAUCUCCUGGUCCCUCUUCCACCCUCUCCUCUUCCACCCUCAGUGGAUGAUAAUCUGAAGGACUGUCUCUUUGUCCCUCUUCCACCCUCUCCUCUUCCACCCUCAGUGGAUGAUAAUCUCAAGACUCCUCCCUUAGCUACUCAGGAGGCCGAGGCGGAAAAACCACCCAAACCCAAGAGGUGGAGGGUGGAUGAGGUGGAACAAUCACCGAAACCCAAGAGGCGGAGGGCGGAUGAGGUGGAACAAUCGCCCAAGCCCAAGAGGCAGAGGGAGGCCGAGGCACAACAAUUACCCAAACCCAAGAGGCGGAGGUUGAGUAAGCUGAGAACACGCCAUUGCACUCAAGCCUGGGCAAUAAGAAUAAAUCCGUGGGUCGAAAAAAAGAAAAAAAUCAAAAAACAAAACAAAACCCACGCUCCAAAAACAAACUAACGAAGAAUAAAUAAAUAAUAUAAAAAUAAAAUAAA